GGACUGUAGCCGGUACCGGCACCGGAGCGCGCCGGGUCCUCGCCGGGUCCCAGCCCCGCGCGUCGGCCCAGCCCAGCCGGGACCCCCCGCGACAUGCGCGUCCCAGCCCUGCGCUGAGCAGGCGGCAAUGUGGGGACUCGGGGCCCGGGGCCCCGACCGGGGGCUGCUGCUGGCGCUGGCGCUGGGCGGGCUGGCGCGGGCCGGGGGCGUCGAGGUGGAGCCCGGCGGCGCGCACGGCGAGAGCGGGGGCUUCCAGGUGGUCACCUUCGAGUGGGCCCACGUGCAGGAUCCCUACGUCAUCGCGCUCUGGAUCCUCGUGGCCAGCUUGGCCAAGAUCGG